GUGGAGGUGCGGGAUUGGGCGGGCUGCCACGGCAUGGAGAAUGGCUCCGCUUCUGUUGCAGCUGGCGGUGCUCGGCGCGGCGCUGGCGGCCGCAGCCCUCGUACUGAUUUCCAUCGUUGCAUUUACAACUGCUACAAAAAUGCCAGCACUCCAUCGACAUGAAGAAGAGAAAUUCUUCUUAAAUGCCAAAGGCCAGAAAGAAACUUUACCCAGCAUAUGGGACUCACCUACCAAACAACUUUCUGUCGUUGUGCCUUCAUACAAUGAAGAAAAACGGUUGCCUGUGAUGAUGGAUGAAGCUCUGAGCUAUCUAGAGAAGAGACAGAAACGAGAUCCUGCGUUCACUUAUGAAGUGAUAGUAGUUGAUGAUGGCAGUAAAGAUCAGACCUCAAAGGUAGCUUUUAAAUAUUGCCAGAAAUAUGGAAGUGACAAAGUACGUGUGAUAACCCUGGUGAAGAAUCGUGGAAAAGGUGGAGCGAUUAGAAUGGGUAUAUUCAGUUCUCGAGGAGAAAAGAUCCUUAUGGCAGAUGCUGAUGGAGCCACAAAGUUUCCAGAUGUUGAGAAAUUAGAAAAGGGGCUAAAUGAUCUACAGCCUUGGCCUAAUCAAAUGGCUAUAGCAUGUGGAUCUCGAGCUCAUUUAGAAAAAGAAUCAAUUGCUCAGCGUUCUUACUUCCGUACUCUUCUCAUGUAUGGGUUCCACUUUCUGGUGUGGUUCCUUUGUGUCAAAGGAAUCAGGGACACACAGUGUGGGUUCAAAUUAUUUACUCGAGAAGCAGCUUCACGGACGUUUUCAUCUCUACACGUUGAACGAUGGGCAUUUGAUGUAGAACUACUGUACAUAGCACAGUUCUUUAAAAUUCCAAUAGCAGAAAUUGCUGUCAACUGGACAGAAAUUGAAGGUUCUAAAUUAGUUCCAUUCUGGAGCUGGCUACAAAUGGGUAAAGACCUACUUUUUAUACGACUUCGAUAUUUGACUGGUGCCUGGAGGCUUGAGCAAACUCGGAAAAUGAAUUAGGUUGUUUGCAGUCUUCAGUUGUGUUCUUAUGCUUCAGUGUCACAUUUCAUUUCAUUUGAAACUAAAAUUUUAAGUAAAGCUGAAAUAAACUUCUUGUCAUUGUCUGCCUUUUGAUAAUUUUAAAGAAAUAACUUUCCAUAAGUAAAAAAUUAUAUAUCUCUUUGGAUAUAAAUGAUUUUUAAAAGAUGUUUAUUUAAAAAGUCA